AACAGUUAGUGUCAGGAGUGGUUCAAGAAAGCAGUCACUAUAAUGGGAUUUUGGUAUUGGACCACCUGCUUCCAGGCUAGCAAUGAGAAUAUCAACACUUGUGGUAGAAAGAAGCACAGACAGUCCUUGGCACAACUGAAGUGCAAUUGUUCAAACUUCACUGCUGCUGAACUGUAUCUUCUGGUGGAUGGAAACACCCUAGUAGGUUCAGUGGAUCAGAUGUUUGAGAUGUAUGGGGGAAAUAUGAGUGGGCUGAUGUUAAGCUUAUUUGAUAUUUUGAAGAAAUGUAAUGAAAGGUUGAAAGUGAUUAAUUUGACAAUUAAAAACUAAGCAUGAAAGCCAAAGGGCCUCCUCAUUAAGAAAUAAAGAGGCUCUUAUCUGCAACUGGAAAGCAGGAAAAGCUGAGGGCUAGGUCCAGGACUUAAUUGUAAGAGUUGCAGGACCUCAAGGAAGAUUAAAUUCUUACUACUGGCAAGUUGGCUCUGCCUAGAACAGGGUGCUAGUUGGGAAAGAGUGGGAUCUUGACACAUGGGAUGGGGACAUCUAUGUUCAUGCACCCCCAAAUCUUUAAUUCCCAAAUUUCCCUGAACCCUCUGAGCCUAGAGAAGUGGCCCUCUCCUCCCUAGGGCUAGUGCUCCUUCCUUGCUUGAAGUUGAAAAGGCCUCCCCACCGCGGGACAUGAGCCCUUUCAAGAUCAGCCCCACUUUCCUGCCUUGCCACUAAGGCAAUAACCAGAUUAAGUUACAACAUAACCCUGCUAGGGACAUGCUUGACCCAUAAUGGAGGAAAAGGACUGCAUUAGUUUGUAGGGCAGCUGUGCUAAGUGGCUUUAACAACUGAAAUCUAUUUUCUUGCAGUUCUGGAGGCUAGAAGUCUGAGAUCAAAGUGUCAGCAUCAUCAGACCAUCACUGUUACAUAAGUACUUUCCCUUCUCUCACACCUGUGGUUGCGUGGGCUUGCCUUAUGACCAACUGAAAGAGUGGGAAAAAGCUUGAGCUUGGUUCAUGACUGGGUUGGAUCAGGACACUGGUGCAAGCCAUAAAAUGGACAGUAGCUGCACUGCAGAGAGUCAAGAAAACUUUUAAGCUAUUUACAGCUUUUAACAGUUAAGUGUACUCCUAUGAACAAAAGUUGGAGCAUAUGUGUUUCUGUCUACCUGAUUUCUACAGAAUUUGGAAACUAUUUGUAUUUUUGGAGUUAAUGGAGUCAGAAGGACCUCCAGAGUCAGAGAGUUCAGAAUUUUUCUCACAGCAAGAAGAGGAAAAUGAAGAAGAAGAAGCCCAAGAACCAGAGGAAACAGGCCCUAAGAACCCCCUUUUACAACCUGCUCUCACAGGGGAUGUAGAGGGUUUGCAGAAGAUAUUUGAGGAUCCUGAGAAUCCUCAUCAUGAACAGGCCAUGCAGCUUCUCUUAGAAGAAGACAUCGUUGGGAGAAAUUUGUUGUAUGCAGCUUGCAUGGCUGGGCAAAGUGACGUGAUUAGAGCUUUGGCAAAAUAUGGUGUGAAUCUGAAUGAAAAAACCACCAGAGGGUACACACUCUUACAUUGUGCUGCAGCCUGGGGUCGUUUGGAAACUUUGAAAGCACUGGUAGAACUGGAUGUUGAUAUAGAAGCUUUGAACUUCCGGGAAGAAAGGGCUCGAGAUGUUGCUGCUAGAUAUUCUCAGACUGAGUGUGUUGAAUUCCUGGACUGGGCAGAUGCAAGGCUGACUCUGAAAAAAUAUAUUGCAAAAGUCUCUUUAGCUGUUACUGACACAGAAAAGGGAUCAGGGAAACUCCUUAAGGAAGACAAGAAUACCAUCCUCAGUGCAUGCCGUGCAAAAAAUGAGUGGUUGGAAACCCAUACAGAAGCUUCCAUUAAUGAGCUUUUUGAGCAGAGACAACAACUGGAAGAUAUUGUGACUCCUAUCUUCACAAAAAUGACUACACCAUGUCAAGUGAAAAGUGCCAAAUCUGUAACAAGCCAUGACCAGAAGAGAAGUCAAGAUGAUACCUCCAACUGAACAUACGUUCUGUAAAAGGCCACAUUUUCUUUUAGUAUCUGAAAGGCAAACCUAUUCAUGCCAUUUGAAAUCGAGAAAACAGAUGUGGGUUUCUUUAAGUAUUUAAGUACAACAUUACAUCGCCCUUGUUUUGUUUGACCUGUUCAGCAUGCUUAUGUCCGGACUCUGGCCUCGCCUCUGCUCCUCCAAGCACAGCCCCAUGUGAGUUUCACGUGCUCCUUCAGGAAAGCACUUGGGUAUAAAUCAUUCGUGAAGACCAUGUGGAGGCUUUAAGAACUACUCAGAGAAUCUAAUAAUUUUCUGUGUAAUUGAGGCAUUCCAUAUAAAAGGACAUAUUUGGCUAUUUCCAGAGAAAAAAUUUGUUCUCCCUGCCUAAAAAGGAAAUCUUAUGGAAUGACACUUGGAGCAAGGAAAUAUUAAGACCAGCUUGGAUUAGGAGCCUCUGGGUACAACUAUCACUUUUUAUGUCCAAAAUUAAAUUUCACCUGUGAGGUGGGGUAUACCUCUGAGUAAAACCCCUCUUUAUCUUUGACCUCCUUCUAUCUGUAAAUUAAUAAACACAAAUCUGUAUAGUUUUAUACUUAGAAGAGUUCUCCUAUUCUGUAAGGCUGGCAAUACAGAUAUUGUAACUGGACUGAAGACCAUUUCCCCUCCCAUUCUGUUUUAUAUUUCCUAGGUUUUAAGUACGAUAGUUGGUUUCAUAUUGGUGGUUUGGAAAGCCUUUUUUCUAAUUUAUUUAAUCAGGCGCCUCAACCUUCUCUUACGUUGUGACUUUAUGGAAAAGUUUUAUAGAAAAGAAGAUGGUUUUUAAAAAGCACUUAUUGUUCGUUCUUAUGGCUUUCUCUUCUUUGUCCUGUUCUGAAAGCUAGUUUUCCCUUAUGGGGAGAAGGAAAAGGAAUGGGUAAUUCAGUAAUACUUUGUCAGUUGACAUUUAUUUAACCAUGGUUUUGAGAUAACCCUGUUUUAAAUGUCUCCCAAAGUUUUUAGUUUUUUAUCCUUUUAAUGUAUGAGCAAUUCAGUUUCAAUUUUUUAAAGCAAAAGAACACUGCAAUAACUUUCAGCCACCUUUUUGGCCGACCCAGUGGGUGUUUAUGGAGCAGUACAAAGAAGACCUGUGUUUGCUCCUUUUUUUUUUUUACCCUCCUUCUCCCUUCUCCCUUUUCCCUUCCCUUCCCCUUCUCCUUCCUCUCCCUUCCUCUCCCUUCCCCUCCCUUCCCCUCCCUUCCCCUCCCUUCCUCUCCCUUCCUCUCCCCUCCCCUCCCUUCCUCUCCCCUCCCCUCCCUUCCUCUCCCCUCCCCUCCCCCUCCUCUUCUCUCUCCUCCUCCUCUUCCCUCUCCAACUCCUUCUUCUUCCUCUCUUAUCUCUCUCUCUCUCUCCACCCCCGCAACCUUCUUGACAGGGUCUGCCUCUCCUGCCCAGGCUGGAAUGCAGUGGAGUUAUCAUGAUCAUAGCUCACUGUAACCUGUAACUCCUGCACUCAAGUGAUCCUCCCACCAUGCUUGGGUAAUUGAAAAAAUAAACAUUUGCAGGCUGGGUGCUGGCUCACACCUGUAAUCCAAGAACUUUGGGAGGCCAAGGCAGGCGGAUCACCUGAGGUCAGCGGUUUGAGACAAGCCUGGCCAACAUGGUGAAACCCUGUCUCUACUAAAAAUACAAAAAUUUAGCUGUAUGUGGUGGCACGUGCCUGUAAUCCCAGUGACUUGGGAGGCUGAGGCAGGAGAAUCACCUGAGCCCGGGAGGUGGAGGUUGCAGUGAGCCGAGAUCGCACCACUGCAUUCCAGCCUGGGUGACAGAGUGAGACUCCAUCUC